GAGGCUCGGCCCGGGGAAAGUGAAAGUUUGCCUGGGUCCUCUCGGCGCCAGAGCCGCUCUCCGCAUCCCAGGACAGCGGUGCGGCCCUCGGCCGGGGCGCCCACUCCGCAGCAGCCAGCGAGCGAGCGAGCGAGCGAGGGCGGCCGACGCGCCCGGCCGGGACCCAGCUGCCCGUAUGACCGCGCCGGGCGCCGCCGGGCGCUGCCCUCCCACGACAUGGCUGGGCUCCCUGCUGUUGUUGGUCUGUCUCCUGGCGAGCAGGAGUAUCACCGAGGAGGUGUCGGAGUACUGUAGCCACAUGAUUGGGAGUGGACACCUGCAGUCUCUGCAGCGGCUGAUUGACAGUCAGAUGGAGACCUCGUGCCAAAUUACAUUUGAGUUUGUAGACCAGGAACAGUUGAAAGAUCCAGUGUGCUACCUUAAGAAGGCAUUUCUCCUGGUACAAGACAUAAUGGAGGACACCAUGCGCUUCAGAGAUAACACCCCCAAUGCCAUCGCCAUUGUGCAGCUGCAGGAACUCUCUUUGAGGCUGAAGAGCUGCUUCACCAAGGAUUAUGAAGAGCAUGACAAGGCCUGCGUCCGAACUUUCUAUGAGACACCUCUCCAGUUGCUGGAGAAGGUCAAGAAUGUCUUUAAUGAAACAAAGAAUCUCCUUGACAAGGACUGGAAUAUUUUCAGCAAGAACUGCAACAACAGCUUUGCUGAAUGCUCCAGCCAAGAUGUGGUGACCAAGCCUGAUUGCAACUGCCUGUACCCCAAAGCCAUCCCUAGCAGUGACCCGGCCUCUGUCUCCCCUCAUCAGCCCCUCGCCCCCUCCAUGGCCCCUGUGGCUGGCUUGACCUGGGAGGACUCUGAGGGAACUGAGGGCAGCUCCCUCUUGCCUGGUGAGCAGCCCCUGCACACAGUGGAUCCAGGCAGUGCCAAGCAGCGGCCACCCAGGAGCACCUGCCAGAGCUUUGAGCCGCCAGAGACCCCAGUUGUCAAGGACAGCACCAUCGGUGGCUCACCACAGCCUCGCCCCUCUGUCGGGGCCUUCAACCCCGGGAUGGAGGAUAUUCUUGACUCUGCAAUGGGCACUAAUUGGGUCCCAGAAGAAGCCUCUGGAGAGGCCAGUGAGAUUCCCGUACCCCAAGGGACAGAGCUUUCCCCCUCCAGGCCAGGAGGGGGCAGCAUGCAGACAGAGCCCGCCAGACCCAGCAACUUCCUCUCAGCAUCUUCUCCACUCCCUGCAUCAGCAAAGGGCCAACAGCCGGCAGAUGUAACUGGUACCGCCUUGCCCAGGGUGGGCCCCGUGAGGCCCACUGGCCAGGACUGGAAUCACACCCCCCAGAAGACAGACCAUCCAUCUGCCCUGCUCAGAGACCCCCCGGAGCCAGGCUCUCCCAGGAUCUCAUCACUGCGCCCCCAGGGCCUCAGCAACCCCUCCACCCUCUCUGCUCAGCCACAGCUUUCCAGAAGCCACUCCUCGGGCAGCGUGCUGCCCCUUGGGGAGCUGGAGGGCAGGAGGAGCACCAGGGAUCGGAGGAGCCCCGCAGAGCCAGAAGGAGGACCAGCAAGUGAAGGGGCAGCCAGGCCCCUGCCCCGUUUUAACUCCGUUCCUUUGACUGACACAGGCCAUGAGAGGCAGUCCGAGGGAUCCUUCAGCCCGCAGCUCCAGGAGUCUGUCUUCCACCUGCUGGUGCCCAGUGUCAUCCUGGUCUUGCUGGCCGUCGGAGGCCUCUUGUUCUACAGGUGGAGGCGGCGGAGCCAUCAAGAGCCUCAGAGAGCGGAUUCUCCCUUGGAGCAACCAGAGGGCAGCCCCCUGACUCAGGAUGACAGACAGGUGGAACUGCCAGUGUAGAGGGAAUUCUAAGCUGGACGCACAGAACAGUCUCUCCGUGGGAGGAGACAUUAUGGGGCGUCCACCACCACCCCUCCCUGGCCAUCCUCCUGGAAUGUGGUCUGCCCUCCACCAGAGCUCCUGCCUGCCAGGACUGGACCAGAGCAGCCAGGCUGGGGCCCCUCUGUCUCAACCCGCAGACCCUUGACUGAAUGAGAGAGGCCAGAGGAUGCUCCCCAUGCUGCCACUAUUUAUUGUGAGCCCUGGAGGCUCCCAUGUGCUUGAGGAAGGCUGGUGAGCCCGGCUCAGGACCCUCUUCCCUCAGGGGCUGCACCCUCCUCUCACUCCCUUCCAUGCCGGAACCCAGGCCAGGGACCCACCGGCCUGUGGUUUGUGGGAAAGCAGGGUGGACGCUGAGGAGUGAAAGAACCCUGCACCCAGAGGGCCUGCCUGGUGCCAAGGUAUCCCAGCCUGGACAGGCAUGGACCUGUCUCCAGAGAGAGGAGCCUGAAGUUCGUGGGGCGGGACAGCGUCGGCCUGAUUUCCCGUAAAGGUGUGCAGCCUGAGAGACGGGAAGAGGAGGCCUCUGGACCUGCUGGUCUGCACUGACAGCCUGAAGGGUCUACACCCUCGGCUCACCUAAGUGCCCUGUGCUGGUUGCCAGGCGCAGAGGGGAGGCCAGCCCUGCCCUCAGGACCUGCCUGACCUGCCAGUGAUGCCAAGAGGGGGAUCAAGCACUGGCCUCUGCCCCUCCUCCUUCCAGCACCUGCCAGAGCUUCUCCAGGAGGCCAAGCAGAGGCUCCCCUCAUGAAGGAAGCCAUUGCACUGUGAACACUGUACCUGCCUGCUGAACAGCCUGCCCCCGUCCAUCCAUGAGCCAGCAUCCGUCCGUCCUCCACUCUCCAGCCUCUCCCCAGCCUCCUGCACUGAGCUGGCCUCACCAGUCGACUGAGGGAGCCCCUCAGCCCUGACCUUCUCCUGACCUGGCCUUUGACUCCCCGGAGUGGAGUGGGGUGGGAGAACCUCCUGGGCCGCCAGCCAGAGCCGGUCUUUAGGCUGUGUUGUUCGCCCAGGUUUCUGCAUCUUGCACUUUGACAUUCCCAAGAGGGAAGGGACUAGUGGGAGAGAGCAAGGGAGGGGAGGGCACAGACAGAGAGGCUACAGGGCGAGCUCUGACUGAAGAUGGGCCUUUGAAAUAUAGGUAUGCACCUGAGGUUGGGGGAGGGUCUGCACUCCCAAACCCCAGCGCAGUGUCCUUUCCCUGCUGCCGACAGGAACCUGGGGCUGAACAGGUUAUCCCUGUCAGGAGCCCUGGACUGGGCUGCAUCUCAGCCCCACCUGCAUGGUAUCCAGCUCCCAUCCACUUCUCACCCUUCUUUCCUCCUGACCUUGGUCAGCAGUGAUGACCUCCAACUCUCACCCACCCCCUCUACCAUCACCUCUAACCAGGCAAGCCAGGGUGGGAGAGCAAUCAGGAGAGCCAGGCCUCAGCUUCCAAUGCCUGGAGGGCCUCCACUUUGUGGCCAGCCUGUGGUGGUGGCUCUGAGGCCUAGGCAACGAGCGACAGGGCUGCCAGUUGCCCCUGGGUUCCUUUGUGCUGCUGUGUGCCUCCUCUCCUGCCGCCCUUUGUCCUCCGCUAAGAGACCCUGCCCUACCUGGCCGCUGGGCCCCGUGACUUUCCCUUCCUGCCCAGGAAAGUGAGGGUCGGCUGGCCCCACCUUCCCUGUCCUGAUGCCGACAGCUUAGGGAAGGGCAGUGAACUUGCAUAUGGGGCUUAGCCUUCUAGUCACAGCCUCUAUAUUUGAUGCUAGAAAACACAUAUUUUUAAAUGGAAGAAAAAUAAAAAGGCAUUCCCCCUUCAUCCCCCUACCUUAAACAUAUAAUAUUUUAAAGGUCAAAAAAGCAAUCCAACCCACUGCAGAAGCUCUUUUUGAGCACUUGGUGGCAUCAGAGCAGGAGGAGCCCCAGAGCCACCUCUGGUGUCCCCCCAGGCUACCUGCUCAGGAACCCCUUCUGUUCUCUGAGAAGUCAAGAGAGGACAUUGGCUCACGCACUGUGAGAUUUUGUUUUUAUACUUGGAAGUGGUGAAUUAUUUUAUAUAAAGUCAUUUAAAUAUCUAUUUAAAAGAUAGGAAGCUGCUUAUAUAUUUAAUAAUAAAAGAAGUGCACAAGCUGC